AAAUCCUCGGCCUCGGUGGCGGUGGUGGACACGUCGAGCCGGGUAGAAGUGGAGGGGCCGUUCGAAGAGUCGUGAGGGGGUGACGGGUUAAGAUUCGGAGAGAGAGGUGCUAGUGGCUGGACUUGACCUGGAAAGAAUCUUCUGCUGACUCUCAACUUUUCCUGGAAAAAAUGGAUCAUUCCCACCAUAUGGGGAUGAGCUAUAUGGACUCCAACAGUACCAUGCAACCUUCUCACCAUCACCCAACCACUUCAGCCUCACACUCCCAUGGUGGAGGAGACAGCAGCAUGAUGAUGAUGCCUAUGACCUUCUACUUUGGCUUUAAGAAUGUGGAACUACUGUUUUCCGGUUUGGUGAUCAAUACAGCUGGAGAAAUGGCUGGAGCUUUUGUGGCAGUGUUUUUACUAGCAAUGUUCUAUGAAGGACUCAAGAUAGCCCGAGAGAGCCUGCUGCGUAAGUCACAAGUCAGCAUUCGCUACAAUUCCAUGCCUGUCCCAGGACCAAAUGGAACCAUCCUUAUGGAGACACACAAAACUGUUGGGCAACAGAUGCUGAGCUUUCCUCACCUCCUGCAAACAGUGCUGCACAUCAUCCAGGUGGUCAUAAGCUACUUCCUCAUGCUCAUCUUCAUGACCUACAACGGGUACCUCUGCAUUGCAGUAGCAGCAGGGGCCGGUACAGGAUACUUCCUCUUCAGCUGGAAGAAGGCAGUGGUAGUGGAUAUCACAGAGCAUUGCCAUUGACAUCAAACUCUAUGGCGUGGCCUUAUCGAUUGCAGUGGGAAGUUGUUGAAGACUUGAAGACGUGAUUCCUGCUCCAAUCAUCCCUUCUUGCUCCUCUUUGUGCACGUACACACACACACACACACACACACACACACACCCCUGCUCAACAGAGGUUUAGUUUACAGUCUCUGAACUAAAGUAGUAACCUCCCAAAUUGUUUUUUCUAAUAAGCUGAGAUUCCCAUUUCUCUUAAGGAGAAGCCACCCAUGAGAUGUCUUUUCCUUCUCCAUCAUCUUAGAGCCAAGUUAUAUGUUCUUGUCUAAUCCAUGUAGCUUUUUGUUCAAUGACUUGAUCAUCUGCUUCCUUUUUGAAUUUUUAACAGAUAGUAAGUAAAUUUGGUGGUUUUUUCCCCUGGGUCAGUGAUGGAAAGGGGUUAACUUCAGCCAGGAUUGAUGGCAGCUGAGGGAAAUUCUUGCCCAACUAAACCCAGAACUCAAACUUAACAUUAGAAAAUAAGGUCCAGGGCCGGACACAGUGGCCCAUGCCUGUAAUCCCAGCACUUUGGGGGGCCAAGGCAGGCUGGAUCACCUGAGGACAGGAGUUCGAGACCAGUCUGGCCAACAUGGGGAAACCCCGUCUCUACUAAAAAUACAAAAAUUAGCCGGGCAUGGUGGUGGGCGCCUGUAAUCCCAGCUACUCAGAAGGCUGAGGCAGGAGAAUCACUUGAACCUAGGAGGCGGAGGUUGCAGUGAGCCAAGAUGGCGCCAUUGCACUCCAGCCUGGGUGACAAGAGUGAAACUCCAUCUCAAAAAAAAAGAAAAGAAGGUCCAGCUUUUGGAUUCAAUGAGUGGGAAAUACAUUGUGCCUUUCUCUAGAUGUGAUACGUUAUACCAAAAUCUUUGUAGUGUGCAGAGCGGUGGUUUGAGACUAAAUACAGGCUUAGAACUUGCAGAGUGUGUAUUCUUGGAUGGCUGAUGCAUCGACUUGCAUUCCCACUUAACACUUUGAUUAGCAUGAACUUGCCAAUCAAAAAAUGACAAUCAAUUUGAGAAAAUAGAAAUAGAUAUUUUUAAAUAAAACCAUUCACAGUUUACUUUGUCUUGAUACCUUGGUUUGUCCCAGCUGAAGUGAAGCAAGAGAGUUUGAAUUAAUUUUUCCAUUAUAAUGUUUUCGCAUGUCUGCCUCUAAAACUGUGAUUUUCAAGCUUUAGCGUGCAUCAGAAUCACCUGUAGGGCUUGUUAAAACACUAAUUGCUGGGCCUCAACCCAAAAGCCCCCAAAGUGGCACUUCUGAGUUCCUGCUGAUGUUACAAGGGACCACACUUUUGAGAAUCUGUGCUUUAAGCUAAGGAAAUAUUGCCUGGUGGGUUGGCUGCCUGGUAUUGGGCAUGGAAAUUUGAAUUGCUGAUUGGUAGAUGGUGUGUCUGGACUUAACUCACGUAGUAAAUACUGCUGAUCAAUACCUAAUCAUUCCACAUUUAUUGAGCUCCACCUGUGUGUAUGUGUACCCAAGCACACAUGUGUGAAGGGCUAUAGCCAAAGUAUUUUUACUAGCCUGUAUGAAAUCACUAGUCCUUAUUUUUAAAGGUCUAUGGUUUCUUGGAAGUAGUUUGAUUGUUGAGAGAGACCUUUGAUCUGCAGUGUAAAUCUACCAGUCAUGGGCCAGAAGGGCAAAAGCCCAGCUUUCUCUUUGGAAAGACUCAGGCUGUGGUUUGUUGAUGGCCAGGUUUUCCUCAGGCUCCAACAACUGUGCUUAUACCAAGCAGAUCCUCAUCCUCCAUAUAAUCAUCUUUGUUAUUCGUGGGGGUUUAAUUACAUUACAAGUGGCCAAAACCCCUGUUCUCAGUGAAGAACCACAUUGGAUUUGUAUUCUGUUCAGUUGUAGUCUACACUGCAGUCUUAUUCCUGGUUCAAACUACCUCUUUAAAUUGAUUUGUCUUGUGCUGGUCUGUUAAAUCCUGCCCUCCUUGGUGCUAGAUCCAGUUGUGCCUCAGGGCAGAGGAAACAAAACACAGCUAUCCUGUUGGCCUGUGUUGUGGUUUUGAAGUUUGUACUUUCUCUGUGGGUGCCAGUUAAAUAUUGGAGAGCAAGGAAUGUGGACUUGUAUGGCUUUGAACCAAGAGAGGGUUAUGAGCCUACUGGAUUGAGGUUAAAAUCCAAGAACCAACAUUUAGAGCUUUGUGCUUUUCUCUCAUUCCAUCACUUUGUAAUGAUGAUACUUAACAUGAGCAGGGUGAAUGACAGGUACUGACGAAGUCCAACACAAAGGUAUAAUACAGCCUGUUGUCUAAAGCCAAGGAGUCAUAAAACCAUGAGAAAUAAAUAGGAAUCAAUAGUUAGUAGUGACAUUGGUGCUCUCUAGAAAUCUCAGCAUGAGCUGCUAUAGAAUACCCUCCCAGCAACAAAACCUAAUCAGUAAGGCCAGCUAGACCCAAUGGCUCAUGCCUGUAAUCCCAACACUUUGGGAGGCCAAGGUGGGAGGAUGGCUUGUGUCCAGAAGUUCGAGACCAGCCUGGACAACAUAGUGAGAUCCUAUCUCUAUAAAAAAUCAAAAAUUAGCCAGGCAUGGUGGUGCAUACCUAUAGUCCUGGCUAUUUGGGAGGCUGAGGCAGGAGGAUUGCUUUAGCCCUGGAGGUCGAGGCUGCAGUAAGCCAUGAUUGCGCCACUGCACUCAGCCCGGGUGACAAAGCAAGACCCUGUCUCAGAAAAAAAGAAAAUUCAAGGCCAGUUAAGACAAAAUGCUAUGACUUUGAAAUUCACAGAAAGAAAUAACAGUUUAGAUUAGGUCUUCAGGUAUUCAGGAUAGAGAUAAUCUCCUGAAAAACCUGAAUUUCAGAGAUUCUUAGACUGGCUGCCAAAGGAUGAAGCUAGUGAAGGAGAAAAAGCUUAAAUUCCAUCUUGAGCUCUUGGAUUGUGAUAAUACAAUGAUUUCAUUAACUUUUCAUUUCUGUAUACCUGUUCAUUUGGAAUUUAAUGCUUGACUUCUUUGUUCAUUUUGGAUCUAAACUUCUCUUUUCUUCCUUCCCCAUUCACAUCUAUUAGAAGACUGCAUCACCAUUUCUUUGGCCCCCUUACUCUGUUGUCCUUUCCCUUUUCUUUCAGUUUUUUUAAUCGCAUGUCUAGUAUAUUAAGUCUCCAUAGCCCUCCUGAUGCAGUAGACAGUGCUAUGCUGUGGAUAUAAUACCAACCAGAAAUUGGCAUUUAUAAACCUGUUAAGAGACUUUAAGCAUGCUUCAAGAGGCAGUUGACCCACUGGAAUUUCUAUAAGGCUGGUACCCUUCCCAGAGUUACAGAAUCUUAGGUGCCGUCUCUAGUCUGUGAGGGAGGAACUCCCAGCAUCCCCAUUGCCCACAAAUGGAAUCCUCACUGUAUCCACUAGGAGAUUAGAAAUUAAGGUUUCUUCACUACUUCUAUGGUAGGGUUGUCUGAAAUUCCCUUUCAGGCUGUGGGUACUGGUCUUGGGUUCUAGUCAUAAGGGGUUCCUUAUAAGGAGCAGGCGGAGGGGAGUACACUUUCAUGUGAUUUAAUUUUGAUCCUGCCCUCUCCAGCUGCUCCUUCAAAAGAUACAUCAAAAGAUAGAAACUCUGGGCUGGGCACAGUGGCUCACACACUUUGGGAGGCCAAGCGGGGGUGCAGAUCACCUGAGGUCAGGAGUUUGAGACCAGCCUGGCCAAUGUGGUGAAACCCCAUCUCUACUAAAAAUACAAAAAUUAGCUGGGCGUGGUGGUGCAUGCCUGUAAUCCCAGCUACUCGGGAGGCUGAGGCAGGAGAAUCGCUUGAACCCAGGAGGCGGAGGUUGCAGUGAGCCAAGAUGGCGCCAUUGCACUCCAGCCUGGGCGACAAGAGCAAAACUCCGUCUCAAAAAAAAAAAAAAGAUACAAAGUCUGCAUUUGAUAUAAUGCCUUAAUUACUGGGUCUACAAUUAAUGUUGACUGUUUUAGAUUGUAAGCUCCUGGAGAGCAGUAUUGCUGUAGUAGGAAUGUUUUAACAGUGUCAUAUGAAAAAGAACAAAAUAAAUAUUUUGAUUUUGUGAUUCUA